AGCCACAGCUGUUGAUUCUCGGACUCUGCGCCCACGGCCUCACCGCGCCCAGUGCCUUGGUUCCGGAUUCUUCCAUAACCGGCUGCCAGUACCGCCUCUCUGACGCCGGGAGUUGCUCCCUAAGAUCUGCUGCCGCCUUUCGCUGGACUUUCCCCCUGGGUGGAGCGGCCGAGGGGGUUUCGAAGCCUGCGUAUCCCUGACUCUUCACCCAGCGCCUCCGUGUCCCUCUACGGGCUCUAAGCGUUCCCCCGCCCCGCUUUUAAGCCGUCCGGUUGCCCUUUGGACCAGCAUCGCUCCGGUCUGUGUGGUAUAAUUCAGUAGUGUUUCCUCAGCACCACAGUCUCUGGCGAUUUCCCUAAUUUAUCUCGGUAUUCAGAGAAAACUUUUUCCUUGGUUACCUUUGUUUUUAACUUGAAAACCAUUAUCGCUGCUUAAGCCUGGAAGGGACCUUCCCAGCACUUUGAGAGGCGGGGCGGGAGGAUCGCUUGAGCCCGGGAGUUGCAGACCAGCCUGGACACCAUAGUGAAACCGCAUCGCUACAAAAAAAAAAAAAAAAAAGUUAAAAAUUAGGGGAGCAGCAGUGAGCACUUGUGGUCUCAGCUACUCGGGAGGCUGAGGCAGGAAGAUCGCUUGAGCCCAGAAGGUCGCUGCUGCAGUAAACCGUGAUCACGUCACAGCACUCCAGCCUAGGCUACAGAAAAAAAGAAAAAGGGCCGGGUGCGGUGGCUCACGCCUGUAAUCUCAACAUUUUGGGAGGCCGAGGCAGGUGUAUCACCUGAAGUCGGUAAUUCGAGACCAGCCUGGCCAACACAGAGGAACCCCGUCUCUACUAAAGAGGAAAUUACGCAUGGUGGCGCAAGCCUGUAAUCCCAGCUACUCCGGAGGCUGAGGCAGGAGAAUCGCUUGAUUCUCGAGUUACAGUGAGCCGAGAUCCGGCGAUUGCCCUCCAGCCUGGGCAACAAGAGCGAAACGUCUCAAAAAAAAAAAGGGAAAAAAGAAAAAGGGGCCUCCAGAAGGAAGUCAUCUGCUCCCUGCUGUGGAGGCUGCAUCUAAUGCUUGUACCGGGGCAGUCAUAUGACAAGUAAGCGAUGCCAGGGCAGGCUCAGGCAUUCUAGAAGAGAGGAAGAAAAGAAGGCAACAGGAACUAGGAGAGAGAAGGACGUGGACAGGAGGAGGUGUUUGACUAGAAAUACAGAUCACUUGGAUUCAGUCGAGUUUGCUUUGCUCCGUGGGAACUGCACCAGAGCUGGAGGUUAGCAUCUUGCAAGGAGGUAGUAACAUAUCCAGUCGUGAAACUGGGAAAGACCAGAGCUCUUGCAUCAGGGAAACAUGUCCCGUCGGAAACAGACAAAUCCAAAUAAAGUUCACUGGGAUCAAGUAUUUGCUGGGCUAGAAGAGCAAGCCCGCCAGGCGAUGAUGAAAACUGAUUUUCCUGGAGACCUUGGCAGUCAGCGACAAGCUAUCCAACAACUAAGAGAUCAGGACUCCAGUAGCAGUGACAGUGAGGGUGAUGAAGAGGAGACGACACAAGAUGAAGUCUCUUCCCACACAUCAGAGGAAGAUGGAGGGGUGGUCAAAGUGGAGAAAGAGUUAGAAAAUACAGAACAGCCUGUUGGUGGGAACGAAGUGGUAGAGCACGAGGUCACAGGGAAUUUGAAUUCUGACCCCUUGCUUGAACUCUGCCAGUGUCCCCUCUGCCAGCUAGACUGCGGGAGCCGGGAGCAGUUGAUUGCUCACGUGUACCAGCACACUGCAGCAGUGGUGAGCGCCAAGAGCUACAUGUGUCCUGUCUGUGGCCGGGCCCUUAGCUCCCCGGGGUCAUUGGGUCGCCACCUCUUAAUCCACUCGGAGGACCAGCGAUCUAACUGUGCUGUGUGUGGAGCCCGGUUCACCAGCCAUGCCACUUUUAACAGUGAGAAACUUCCUGAAGUACUAAAUAUGGAAUCCCUACCCACAGUCCACAAUGAGGGUCCCUCCAGUGCUGAGGGGAAGGAUAUUGCCUUUAGUCCUCCAGUGUACCCUGCUGGAAUUCUGCUUGUGUGCAACAACUGUGCUGCCUACCGUAAACUGCUGGAAGCCCAGACUCCCAGUGUACGCAAGUGGGCUCUACGUCGACAGAAUGAGCCUUUGGAAGUACGGCUGCAGCGGCUGGAACGAGAGCGCACGGCCAAGAAGAGCCGGCGGGACAAUGAGACCCCCGAGGAGCGGGAGGUGAGGCGCAUGAGGGACCGUGAAGCCAAGCGCUUGCAGCGCAUGCAGGAGACAGACGAGCAGCGGGCACGCCGGCUGCAGCGGGAUCGGGAGGCCAUGAGGCUGAAGCGGGCCAAUGAAACCCCGGAAAAGCGGCAGGCCCGGCUCAUCCGAGAGCGAGAGGCCAAGCGGCUCAAGAGGAGGCUGGAGAAAAUGGACAUGAUGUUGCGAGCUCAGUUUGGCCAGGACCCUUCUGCCAUGGCAGCCUUAGCAGCUGAAAUGAACUUCUUCCAGCUGCCUGUAAGUGGGGUGGAGUUGGACAGCCAGCUUCUGGGCAAGAUGGCCUUUGAAGAGCAGAACAGCAGCUCUCUGCACUGAACCACACCCUCCUGCCUGCCCUCCUUCCCACCUACCUACCCACCCACCCACACCCACAGCCACGAGGACCAGUGCUGCUGCCACCCACGAGGCCCUGUCCUUGCUGCCAGAGGCAGGCCUGGGUUUAUUGCAGGUGGACCUGAGCAGCCCUUGCAUAUGGGAACAGGAUGAUGGGGUCAGGAGGGACCUGGCUCAAGGCAGCUCUGGACAAGGGAGCAGGCAGUCCAGAGAACUGGCCUCCCCAGCCCACUGCCACAGGCUGUGCUUCUAGGACUGUGGGGCCCCUGUGUGGCCCAUGAAGUUGUGAAGUCAAAUAAAUUAAUUUUAUCUUUACUGCC